AAUUCUCGCGAGAUUUACCGGCAGCCAUCUUCUUGGGGGUGCUGGGAGCCGGGAAGACCCCCUGAAUCGUUCCCAUUGAGCUGCCCUUCGCCUUCGCUUUCUUUACUUUUGCCUUUUCGACGUAGCCAACAAGCACCUGGUCCCGAGGCUGAGAGAAGGCUCGGGUCUAAGCGCGUGUCGCGCUUCCGGUCUGGGUAGAUUUGCUGGGGAAGAGGGAAGGGGGAGGGCCCGGGCAAACCGUUGCUGUUUCAGCCCGGGCUGGGGGCCGGGGACGGGGAGCUCCUGGCACCCCGUGCACUUGUGGCCUGCGGCGGUCCUUGCAGAGCUGUUCGCCGACCGGGGCCCGCGGGAACCUGCCACCGGCGCCUCCCACCGCGGCCCACGCGGGCGGCGCGCGGAGGAGGGGGCGGGGGCAGCGGCGGCUGUAGCGGCCGCGACCUGGGCGGGCGGAGGAGUGUGACGGGCCUUAGGGCCGCUGUGGAUGGUUUCUAAAAUGAUCAUUGAAAACUUCGAGGCACUCAAGUCCUGGCUCAGCAAGACUCUCGAGCCCAUCUGUGAUGCAGAUCCAUCCGCCCUAGCAAAAUAUGUUCUGGCUUUGGUAAAGAAAGACAAAAGUGAAAAAGAGUUAAAGGCAUUAUGUAUUGAUCAGCUGGAUGUAUUUCUUCAGAAAGAGACACAGAUAUUUGUGGAAAAACUUUUUGAUGCUGUGAAUACAAAGAGUUACCUACCUCCUCCAGAGCAGCCAUCAUCAGGAAGCCUGAAGGUAGAAUUUUUUCCACACCAAGAAAAAGAUAUAAAGAAGGAAGAGAUCACUAAGGAGGAAGAGCGAGAGAAGAAGUUUUCUAGAAGGCUAAAUCACAGUCCUCCCCAGUCAAGCUCCCGAUACAGGGAAAAUAGAAGCCGUGAUGAGAGGAAAAAAGAUGAUCGUUCUCGCAAAAGAGAUUAUGAUCGAAACCCUCCUCGAAGAGAUUCAUACAGAGACCGGUACAAUAGAAGACGAGGGCGGAGUCGCAGUUAUAGCAGGAGUCGAAGUCGAAGUUGGAGUAAAGAGAGGCUUCGUGAGAGGGACAGAGAUAGAAGCAGGACUAGAAGCAGAAGCAGAACACGAAGCAGGGAAAGGGAUCUGGUAAAACCUAAAUAUGACCUGGAUAGAACAGAUCCAUUAGAAAAUAAUUAUACUCCAGUCUCUUCGGUACCUAGUAUUUCAUCUGGCCACUACCCUGUACCUACUUUGAGCAGCACUAUUACAGUAAUUGCUCCUACUCAUCAUGGAAACAACACUACCGAAAGUUGGUCUGAAUUUCAUGAAGACCAAGUGGACCAUAACUCUUACGUAAGACCACCCAUGCCAAAGAAACGGUGUAGAGACUAUGAUGAAAAGGGUUUUUGUAUGAGAGGAGACAUGUGUCCUUUUGAUCAUGGAAGUGAUCCAGUAGUUGUAGAAGAUGUGAAUCUUCCUGGUAUGCUGCCUUUCCCAGCACAGCCUCCUGUUGUUGAAGGACCACCUCCUCCUGGACUCCCCCCACCUCCACCAAUUCUUACACCCCCACCUGUGAAUCUCAGGCCCCCAGUACCACCGCCAGGUCCAUUGCCACCCAGUCUCCCACCUGUUACAGAUGAUAUUUCUUAUUCUUUGGUUUUGACAGGACCACCACCUCCACUUCCUCCUUUGCAGCCAUCUGGCAUGGAUGCUCCUCCAAACUCUGCAACCAGUUCUGUUCCUACUGUAGUAACAACUGGCAUUCAUCACCAGCCUCCUCCUGCUCCACCCUCUCUUUUUACUGCAGUUUUUGUAUUACCAGAUACAUAUGACACAGAUGGCUACAAUCCUGAAGCCCCAAGCAUAACAAACACUUCCAGACCUAUGUAUAGACACAGAGUGCAUGCACAAAGGCCCAACUUGAUAGGACUAACAUCAGGGGAUAUGGAUUUGCCACCCAGAGAAAAGCCUCCCAAUAAAAGCAGUAUGAGGAUAGUAGUGGACUCAGAAUCAAGGAAAAGAACCAUUGGUUCUGGAGAGCCUGGAGUUCCUACAAAGAAGACUUGGUUUGAUAAACCAAAUUUUAAUAGAACAAACAGCCCAGGCUUUCAGAAGAAGGUUCAAUUUGGAAAUGAAAAUACCAAGCUUGAACUUAGAAAAGUUCCUCCAGAAUUAAAUAAUAUCAGCAAACUUAAUGAACAUUUUAGUCGAUUUGGAACCUUGGUUAACUUACAGGUUGCUUAUAAUGGUGAUCCUGAAGGUGCCCUAAUCCAAUUUGCAACAUACGAAGAAGCAAAGAAAGCAAUAUCAAGUACGGAAGCAGUAUUAAACAAUCGCUUUAUUAAGGUUUAUUGGCACAGAGAAGGAAGCACCCAACAGUUACAAACUACUUCUCCAAAGGUAAUGCAGCCUUUAGUCCAGCAGCCCAUUUUGCCUGUUGUGAAGCAGUCAGUCAAAGAGCGGCUGGGUCCAGUACCUUCAAGUACUAUUGAACCUGCAGAAGCCCAGAGUGCCUCUUCAGACCUUCCUCAGAAUGUAACUAAGUUAUCUGUGAAGGACAGGUUGGGUUUUGUAUCAAAGCCAUCUGUUUCAGCAACUGAAAAGGUGUUGUCUACAUCUACUGGCCUAACAAAAACAGUGUAUAAUCCAGCUGCUUUGAAGGCUGCACAGAAAACCUUACUUGUUUCCACCUCUGCAGUUGAUAAUAAUGAAGCACAGAAAAAAAAACAGGAGGCAUUGAAACUUCAGCAGGAUGUAAGGAAAAGGAAACAAGAAAUUUUAGAAAAGCACAUUGAAACACAGAAGAUGUUAAUUUCAAAACUGGAGAAAAACAAAACAAUGAAGUCUGAAGAUAAAGCAGAAAUAAUGAAAACUUUAGAGGUUUUGACAAAAAAUAUUACCAAGUUGAAAGAUGAGGUCAAAGCUGCUUCUCCUGGACGCUGUCUUCCAAAAAGUAUAAAAACCAAGACUCAGAUGCAGAAGGAAUUACUUGACACAGAACUGGAUUUAUAUAAGAAGAUGCAGGCUGGAGAAGAAGUCACUGAACUUAGGAGAAAGUAUACAGAAUUACAGCUGGAAGCUGCCAAACGAGGGAUUCUUUCAUCUGGUCGGGGCAGAGGAAUUCAUUCAAGAGGUCGAGGUGCAGUUCAUGGCCGAGGCAGGGGGCGAGGGCGAGGGCGAGGUGUGCCUGGUCAUGCUGUGGUGGAUCACCGUCCCAGGGCAUUGGAGAUUUCUGCAUUUACGGAGAGCGAUAGAGAAGAUCUUCUUCCUCAUUUUGCGCAAUAUGGUGAAAUUGAAGAUUGUCAGAUUGAUGAUUCCUCACUUCAUGCAGUAAUUACAUUCAAGACAAGAGCAGAAGCUGAAGCAGCUGCAGUUCAUGGAGCUCGUUUCAAAGGGCAAGAUCUAAAACUGGCAUGGAAUAAACCAGUAACUAAUAUUUCAGCUGUUGAAACAGAAGAAGUUGAGCCUGAUGAAGAAGAACAGAGAGAGAUCAUCAUUGCCUGAAUUUAGCUUUGUGACUGCAAGAGCAAGACCAGUUCCUGUCUGGAGACGACUGUUACAAUAAUAUCAUCCUAUUAUUUUAUGUUCACUCUUUAUCAAUUUGAACAGAUGUUUACAUGUACUAUAAUUAGCAUUUUAUCUCUACAGUUCUCUAAGAGUACAUCUGAGUCCAAAGUGUAUCUGAAUGUGUGCUCUGACCUUAUUCUUAAAUGUUUUCUCCCCAUACUUUAUAGCCAUUUAUUUUUUAAACACCUUAAGAAGGAACGAAAAAGUUCUCUUGGAUGACGUAUAUUCAAGUCUGAGCCAAAUUGAGGAUUGUGUCUAGGAAAUCUGUAAAGCCAUACUACUGUGUUCAUUAGCAUGAGCAAUUUAAAAUGAAAAUGAAUUAAAAAGUUAAACAUGAGUUUGGUUUUAAUUUUGGGGGGAUCUUAAGAUAUAUUUCUGGGAGUAGGAUAGCCACUGAAAAUAAUUUUGAAUAGAUGAUAAAGUACUUUUUUAUGUACUGUAAUAGCUUGUGCAUUUCUUCUGAAUAUACUUUCUGAUGUUGCCAAGGUCAUUUACCCAAAUAUUUUUUUAAAAAUUCUUAGCCCUUCAAAACCAACAAAGAAAAUAAUUUUCUUCCAAGUGACAAAUGAUGAUCUGUGGAUUAUAAAUAUUUUAAAAAUUAUAUGUCUUAACAUAAUUUUUUCACAUUUUUUUGACUUUCAAUCAAGACAUCGAAGACGACCUUUAAAGCAAGAGGAAAUAGUGUUGUGUGCCUAACAUUGGUAAAGACUAGUUUUUAACCAUUUUAAGAAGUGUAUGUCCAAAUUAUUUAUAAGCAGUAUGACUUAAUAUGGCUUAGAAUUACUUAUAAAGAAUCUGAUUAAAUCUCAUCCUAAAUAUGUAGCCACAAUAUCUUUUUUAUAAUGGGACUAUAAGAAAUGUUUGCACUUAGUUUCUGAGUAUUCCUUCAUAGAUUCUCAGGAGGCAUUUAAAAAGUUGGAAGCUAUACUUGGUAGUAACUAUAUUAGAAAAGUCCAAUUGACACUGAUUUUUAUUCACCCUUGUUUUAUUUUUAUCCAGCCAUACUACCUUUAUCACUUUUUUUUUUUUUUUUGGUGCAAAGCUUAACAUUCUGCAAACUUUUUUUCCCCUUGAGUAUGCAUUGCAUUUGUCAUGAAGAGUAAAAAGAAUGUAAUAAACACAUCAGUCAUAAUGUAAAUUAACUGUUUUGAUCCACAUUGGUUGGAUACAGCAUGGUUAAUUCUAGGCUUGGUUAAAAAUACAUAAUUUGGAAAGUCUUCUAAUAUUUUAAAGACCUAGUAGUUUACAAGGCCUUUUUUUGUUGUUGUUGUUAGACUUUUGGUUCACAUUUACAAACUAGCCACAGGGUGUUCAUAAAUAUUUCCCCAAAUUAGUUGAGUAUUUUUAAUUGUAAACAAAGAAUUUUCUGCCCCUACUACACUGGUUUACUGCUAGGGUAAAGACCAUUGUCUGAAGACACUAAACUUGGUGUUAACAGUGUUGAUUGUUUAAUGGAUAUGGACUACAUGCCACUACCUGCAACUUUGUCAUCCUGGAGUUUUUGUUUGGUUUGGUUUGAUUUUUCACUUUUUGCUUUUAAAAUUAAAAACAAAGCAAAACAAAAUUGAAGAUACCAUUGAGAAUCAGAAUUCAAGAUGACUUGAUUCUCACUAAGAUCACUGCGCUUUUUUAAAAUUGCUUUGAGAUCUAGUCAGUUACAUAUUUAAAAUCCCCGUGUUGAUUAGAGAUAAGGUUUUCAUUAUUUUAUUUUCCUAAAUAGGAUUCUCAUGGAGCUAUUGUAGAUAACUGUACAGAAUCACUUUUGUGUAAUUGAAUGAAGCAGUUUCCUCUGCAUGAUUGCAUAAUGAAAGCCUUUUAUAUAUCUAUAUUUUUCAAUACUUAGAUUUUACACUAUUAAGCUGCUCUAGUCAUGCUAUAUUUGUUUUUUUAAUAGAGUUUAUAAAUAUUUAUGCUCAAAAUACAGAUCAACUGAAUAUUUUUGGUCUUGUUUACAAGAUAAAUCAUACUUUAAAAUGAUACAGGCCCCUCAAGUGUCUUAGGAAAAAGUCAUUGGUGCUAUAAAACCUUUCAGUAUCAUUUUUGAACCCAUUGUUCAGACUUUGCUAGGUUUUAAUCUGAUUCCUUGUGAUUUAUUAUAAUGUAGCAGCAUACUUAUAAAAGUGGUCUGUGCUGAGUCAGAUAGAGAGCCCAGCCCAUUAGAAACACAUCAUAAUUUAAGAAUAUGAUGCAGAAUGCCCUUACACUUAUUUGUGCCCAGCUUCCCAAAAAGAAAAUUGUUUUGUUAAGAGGAAGGCAGUUAAUUUGGCUAGAAUCCAAAAACUCAUUCAGCAUGGCUGUUUUCCCUUAUUUCAAAUGAAAAACUUUUCUAAUACUAAAAUAUGUAAUCCUGCUUUGCUUUAAAUUCCCAUGUCUGUCACUCAACAGGAGGCAUAGUGAUUCUUAAAUAUUUACGGAACAUUUGGUGAGUUGUAAAGAGAAGUAUUAUUGCAUUGUAGGUUUUUGCAUUGAUGUGUCGAUUUUUUUGUUUUGUCCCAAGAUUUCCUUCCAGCACCUUAAUGAAUGUUCAUAUGAUAGAAUGUUUUAAGUAUCAGCAAAGCAUUCAUGGAUGCCUGCUUUUCAUUCUCAGAAGGCUAAACCUGUUUUGGGUAUGAUGCUACUUCAGAACAUAUUGUCUGGCACAAGAUUUCUUCUAAUAAGUGGUUUAUUUAAACUCAAUUUCGGUGGACUGUUGAAUUGAAAAACACCAAAGGAGUCUUCUUGUCUGGAGACUGGAUUGUUCCAGUUUUAAAUACCUGUGCCCAUAAGUAUCCCAUUUCAUGAAUGUGUGUUGGCAUGGGGAAAAAAUUUCCCUGCUCUUUGAGUGGAGCGAAAGCAAUUGGUUAAGCUGUAGCAGCUUUUUUGUUUAUUUUUUUAAAGUAAUAAUAAAACUUGAACUGAAAAAAGAUAAAACUUGAACUAGAAUACUACUCUUGUAUGCUUAGAAUGUUUAUAGUGUUAAAUGUUUAUGUGGGGUUGUCAACAUUUUUAUUAUUUAUAGUUGAAUUAUGUUUUGUUAAAUCCAUAUUGUUUAUUAUUUUUAUAUUUUGAAAAUUUUUAAAAUAAAAGUCUUACUAAAAACA